AGACGGUCGCCGCCGCGUUUGCGCAGGGGGAGCUGGUCGCCGCCGCGGCCGCCUGGAAUUGUGGGAGUUGUGUCUGCCACUCGGCUGCCGGAGGCCGAAGGCCAGCUAUUACUUCUCUACUGAGGCCAACUGUGAGCCCUGGUGUGUUUCAUUGGCAGGAGAAGAGGCUAAUUAAGUGAAACUGAAAGGGCCCAAUCCCCACCCCCAGUCUUGUCUGAAUUGUGUGGAAGACAUGAGGCACUGAGAGAGGUGGGGGCCGAGUGGCCUCCUCCCACCUGCUCCCCAAACAUCUGCUCUGGGCUGCAGUAAGCUGGCAAUACAGAUUGGGCAUAUCUCUUGUUGGAUGGCUGGACCCACCAUGGUAGAUGGAGGCUUCAGAAUUAUCUAGAAGUGGUAGAAGACUCGUUAUACCUCUAUGCAGGAAAUGUCUGACAUGUCCCUGACUAUGGCUCCCCAGAGCCUGCCUUCAUCUAGGAUGGCUCCUCUGGGCAUGCUGCUUGGGCUGCUGAUGGCCGCCUGCUUCACCUUCUGCCUCAGUCAUCAGAACCUGAAGGAGUUUGCCCUGACCAACCCAGAGAAGAGCAGCACCAAAGAAACAGAGAGAAAAGAAACCAAAGCCGAGGAGGAGCUGGAUGCCGAAGUCCUGGAGGUGUUCCACCCGACGCAUGAGUGGCAGGCCCUUCAGCCAGGGCAGGCUGUCCCUGCAGGAUCCCACGUACGGCUGAAUCUUCAGACUGGGGAAAGAGAGGCAAAACUCCAAUAUGAGGACAAGUUCCGAAAUAAUUUGAAAGGCAAAAGGCUGGAUAUCAACACCAACACCUACACAUCUCAGGAUCUCAAGAGUGCACUGGCAAAAUUCAAGGAGGGGGCAGAGAUGGAGAGUUCAAAGGAAGACAAGGCAAGGCAGGCUGAGGUAAAGCGGCUCUUCCGCCCCAUUGAGGAACUGAAGAAAGACUUUGAUGAGCUGAAUGUUGUCAUUGAGACUGACAUGCAGAUCAUGGUACGGCUGAUCAACAAGUUCAAUAGUUCCAGCUCCAGUUUGGAAGAGAAGAUUGCUGCGCUCUUUGAUCUUGAAUAUUAUGUCCAUCAGAUGGACAAUGCGCAGGACCUGCUUUCCUUUGGUGGUCUUCAAGUGGUGAUCAAUGGGCUGAACAGCACAGAGCCCCUCGUGAAGGAGUAUGCUGCGUUUGUGCUGGGCGCUGCCUUUUCCAGCAACCCCAAGGUCCAGGUGGAGGCCAUCGAAGGGGGAGCCCUGCAGAAGCUGCUGGUCAUCCUGGCCACGGAGCAGCCGCUCACUGCAAAGAAGAAGGUCCUGUUUGCACUGUGCUCCCUGCUGCGCCACUUCCCCUAUGCCCAGCGGCAGUUCCUGAAGCUCGGGGGGCUGCAGGUCCUGAGGACCCUGGUGCAGGAGAAGGGCACGGAGGUGCUCGCCGUGCGCGUGGUCACACUGCUCUACGACCUGGUCACGGAGAAGAUGUUCGCCGAGGAGGAGGCUGAGCUGACCCAGGAGAUGUCCCCAGAGAAGCUGCAGCAGUAUCGCCAGGUACACCUCCUGCCAGGCCUGUGGGAACAGGGCUGGUGCGAGAUCACGGCCCACCUCCUGGCGCUGCCCGAGCAUGAUGCCCGUGAGAAGGUGCUGCAGACACUGGGCGUCCUCCUGACCACCUGCCGGGACCGCUACCGUCAGGACCCCCAGCUCGGCAGGACACUGGCCAGCCUGCAGGCUGAGUACCAGGUGCUGGCCAGCCUGGAGCUGCAGGAUGGUGAGGACGAGGGCUACUUCCAGGAGCUGCUGGGCUCUGUCAACAGCUUGCUGAAGGAGCUGAGAUGAGGCCCCACACCAGGACUGGACUGGGAUGCCGCUAGUGAGGCUGAGGGGUGCCAGCGUGGGUGGGCUUCUCAGGCAGGAGGACAUCUUGGCAGUGCUGGCUUGGCCAUUAAAUGGAAACCUGAAGGCCAUCCUCUUUCUGCUGUGUGUCUGUGUAGACUGGGCACAGCCCUGUGGCCGGGGGGUCAGGUGAGUGGUUGGGUGAUGGGCUCUGCUGACGUGCAGGGCUCAGCCCAGGGCAUCCAGGAACAGGCUCCAGGGCAGGAACCUGGGCCCAGGAGUUGCAAGUCUCUGCUUCUUACCAAGCAGCAGCUCUGUACCUUGGGAAGUCGCUUAAUUGCUCUGAGCUUGUUUCCUCAUCUGUCAGGAGUGCCAUUAAAGGAGAAAAAUCACGUA